CUGUCCUCACCUUUGUCCUUGCGCAGCCGGUGGUUGAUAUCCGCUGUAUCCAUCCCCGAGAGGGACCUGGUACCUCUACCCAGGUUUCUAUCGCUCUGUCUCCUGCGCUGUGCCCUUCUGUAGUCACAGGAGCUGUAGAGAGGACCCCAGGACAUCUGAAAGCCAGGAAAUGCCUCCUCUACACAUGUGAGAUGUUUCAGGACCCUGUGGCCUGUGAGGAUGUUGCUGUGAACUUCACCCAGGAGGAGUGGGCUUUGCUGGAUAUUUCGCAGAGGAAACUCUACAGGGAAGUGAUGCUGGAAACUUUCAGGAACCUGACCUCUAUAGGGAAAAAGUGGAAAGACCAGAACAUUGAAUAUGAGUACCAAAACCCCAGGAGAAACUUCAGGAGUCUCAUAGAAGGGAAUGUCAAUGAAAUUAAAGAAGACAGUCAUUGUGGAGAAACUUUUACCCAGGUUCCAGAUGACAGGCUGAACUUCCAGGAGAAGAAAGCUUCUCCUGAAGCAAAAUCAUGUGAUAACUUUGUAUGUGGAGAAGUUGGCAUAGGUAACUCAUCUUUUAAUAUGAACAUCAGAGGUGACAUUGGGCACAAGGCAUACGAGUAUCAGGACUAUGCACCAAAGCCAUAUAAGUGUCAACAACCUAAGAAAGCCUUCAGAUAUCACCCCUCCUUUAGAACACAAGAAAGGAAUCACACCGGAGAGAAACCCUAUGCUUGUAAAGAAUGUGGAAAAACCUUUAUUUCCCAUUCAGGCAUUCGAAGACGCAUGGUAAUGCACAGUGGGGAUGGACCUUAUAAAUGUAAGUUUUGUGGGAAAGCUGUCCAUUGUCUCAGAUUAUAUCUUAUCCAUGAAAGAACUCACACUGGAGAGAAACCGUAUGAAUGUAAACAAUGUGUUAAAUCCUUUAGUUAUUCUGCUACCCAUCGAAUACAUGAAAGAACUCACACUGGAGAAAAGCCUUAUGAAUGUCAGCAAUGUGGGAAAGCAUUCCAUAGUUCCAGUUCUUUUCAAGCACAUAAAAGAACCCACACUGGGGGAAAGCCAUAUGAAUGUAAACAAUGUGGCAAAUCCUUCAGUUGGUGUCAUUCCUUUCAAAUACAUGAAAGAACUCACACUGGGGAGAAGCCCUGUGAAUGUAGCAAAUGUAAUAAAGCAUUCCGUAGUUACAGAUCCUAUCUUAGACAUAAAAGGAGUCACACGGGAGAGAAGCCUUAUCAAUGUAAGGAAUGUAGAAAAGCAUUCACGUAUCCCAGUUCCCUUCGUAGACAUGAAAGGACCCACUCUGCGAAAAAACCUUAUGAAUGUAAGCAGUGUGGGAAAGCAUUAUCUUAUAAGUUUUCAAACACACCUAAGAAUGCGCUCUGGAGAAAGACCUUAUAAAUGUUAGAUAUGUGGGAAAGGCCUUUAUUCUGCCAAGUCAUUUCGAAGACAUGAAAAAACUCACACUGGAGAGAAACCCUAUAAAUGCAUGCCAUGUGGUAAAGCCUUCAAUCUUUCCAGUUCCUUUCAGUAUCAUGAAAGGACUCACACUGGAGAGAAACCCUAUGAGUGUAAGCAAUGUGGGAAAGCCUUCAGAUGUGCCCCACACCUUCGAAGGCAUGGUAGGACUCACUGGAGAGAAACCCUAUGAGUGUAAGGAAUGUGGGAAAGCCUUCAGAUCUGCCUCACACCUUCAAAUUCAUGAAAGGACACAAACACACAUAAGAAUACACUCUGGAGAAAGACCUUAUAAAUGUAAGACAUGUGGGAAAGGCUUUUAUUCUCCCACGUCAUUUCAAAGACAUGAAAAAACUCACACUGCAGAGAAACCCUAUGAAUGCAAGCAAUGUGGUAAAGCCUUCAGUAGUUCCAGUUCCUUUUGGUACCAUGAAAGGACUCACACUGGAGAGAAACCCUAUGAGUGUAAGCAAUGUGGGAAAGCCUUCAGAUCUGCCUCAAUCCUUCAAAUGCAUGCUGGGACUCACCCUGAAGAGAAGCCCUACGAGUGUAAGCAAUGUGGGAAAGCCUUCAGAUCUGCCCCACACCUUCGAAUCCAUGGUAGAACUCACACUGGAGAGAAACCCUAUGAGUGUAAGGAAUGUGGGAAAGCCUUCAGAUCUGCCAAGAACCUUCGAAUUCAUGAAAGGACACAAACACACGUAAGAAUGCACUCUGUAGAAAGACCUUAUAAAUGUAAGAUAUGUGGGAAAGGCUUUUAUUCUGCCAAGUCAUUUCAAAUACCUGAAAAAUCUUACACUGGAGAGAAACCCUAUGAGUGUAAGCAAUGUGGGAAAGCCUUUAUUUCUUUCACUUCUUUUCGAUAACAUGAAAGGACUCACACUGGAGAGAAACCCUAUGAGUGUAAGCAAUGUGGAAAAACCUUCAGAUCUACCUCACACCUUCGAAAACAUGGUAGGACUCACACUGGAUAGAAACCAAAGCAGGUGAAUCACCUGAGGUCAGGAGUUCAAGACUGGCCUGAUCAAUAUGAUGAAACCCCUGUCUCUACUAAAACUACAAAAAUUGGCCAGGCGUGGUGGCCUGCUUCUGUAAUCCUAGCUAGUUGGGAGGCUGGCACAGGAGAAUCGCUUGAAUCUGGGGGGCAGAGGUUGCAGUGAGCCAAGAUUGUGCCAUUGCACUCUAGCCUGGGCAACAGGAGCAAAACUCCGUCUCAAAAAAAAAAAAAAAAAAGACUUGGCCUUGUGGUGAGGGGAUGUCAGCUCUAGACUCCUGGAGCUGUUUUUGCCUUAUUCUCUAAAGACUAAAAUAUUUCAUAAAAUGUAUGGGUGCUGUUUACCAGAAAGUACGUUGGGUAAAACAUAGAAAUUCAUUUAUACCUUAGAAAGCUAUUUUUUUCAGGUUGGUUUAGUGAGUCACAGGAAGCUAAUAAAUUACAAUAAUAAUGUAAA